AGACACAGCUCUGCGUCCUCGAGCGGGACAGAUCCAAGUUGGGAGCAGCUCUGCGUGCGGGGCCUCAGAGAAUGAGGCCGGCGUUCGCCCUGUGCCUCCUCUGGCAGGCGCUCUGGCCCGGGCCGGGCGGCGGCGAACACCCCACUGCCGACCGUGCUGGCUGCUCGGCCUCGGGGGCCUGCUACAGCCUGCACCACGCUACCAUGAAGCGGCAGGCGGCCGAGGAGGCCUGCAUCCUGCGAGGUGGGGCGCUCAGCACCGUGCGUGCGGGCGCCGAGCUGCGCGCUGUGCUCGCGCUCCUGCGGGCAGGCCCAGGGCCCGGAGGGGGCUCCAAAGACCUGCUGUUCUGGGUCGCACUGGAGCGCAGGCGUUCCCACUGCACCCUGGAGAACGAGCCUUUGCGGGGUUUCUCCUGGCUGUCCUCCGACCCCGGCGGUCUCGAAAGCGACACGCUGCAGUGGGUGGAGGAGCCCCAACGCUCCUGCACCGCGCGGAGAUGCGCGGUACUCCAGGCCACCGGUGGGGUCGAGCCCGCAGGCUGGAAGGAGAUGCGAUGCCACCUGCGCGCCAACGGCUACCUGUGCAAGUACCAGUUUGAGGUCUUGUGUCCUGCGCCGCGCCCCGGGGCCGCCUCUAACUUGAGCUAUCGCGCGCCCUUCCAGCUGCACAGCGCCGCUCUGGACUUCAGUCCACCUGGGACCGAGGUGAGUGCGCUCUGCCGGGGACAGCUCCCGAUCUCAGUUACUUGCAUCGCGGACGAAAUCGGCGCUCGCUGGGACAAACUCUCGGGCGAUGUGUUGUGUCCCUGCCCCGGGAGGUACCUCCGUGCUGGCAAAUGCGCAGAGCUCCCUAACUGCCUAGACGACUUGGGAGGCUUUGCCUGCGAAUGUGCUACGGGCUUCGAGCUGGGGAAGGACGGCCGCUCUUGUGUGACCAGUGGGGAAGGACAGCCGACCCUUGGGGGGACCGGGGUGCCCACCAGGCGCCCGCCGGCCACUGCAACCAGCCCCGUGCCGCAGAGAACAUGGCCAAUCAGGGUCGACGAGAAGCUGGGAGAGACACCACUUGUCCCUGAACAAGACAAUUCAGUAACAUCUAUUCCUGAGAUUCCUCGAUGGGGAUCACAGAGCACGAUGUCUACCCUUCAAAUGUCCCUUCAAGCCGAGUCAAAGGCCACUAUCACCCCAUCAGGGAGCGUGAUUUCCAAGUUUAAUUCUACGACUUCCUCUGCCACUCCUCAGGCUUUCGACUCCUCCUCUGCCGUGGUCUUCAUAUUUGUGAGCACAGCAGUAGUAGUGUUGGUGAUCUUGACCAUGACAGUACUGGGGCUUGUCAAGCUCUGCUUUCACGAAAGCCCCUCUUCCCAGCCAAGGAAGGAGUCUAUGGGCCCGCCGGGCCUGGAGAGUGAUCCUGAGCCCGCUGCUUUGGGCUCCAGUUCUGCACAUUGCACAAACAAUGGGGUGAAAGUCGGGGACUGUGAUCUGCGGGACAGAGCAGAGGGUGCCUUGCUGGCGGAGUCCCCUCUUGGCUCUAGUGAUGCAUAGGGAAACAGGGGACAUGGGCACUCCUGUGAACAGUUUUUCACUUUUGAUGAAACGGGGAACCAAGAGGAACUUACUUGUGUAACUGACAAUUUCUGCAGAAAUCCCCCUUCCUCUAAAUUCCCUUUACUCCACUGAGGAGCUAAAUCAGAACUGCACACUCCUUCCCUGAUGAUAGAGGAAGUGGAAGUGCCUUUAGGAUGGUGAUACUGGGGGACCGGGUAGUGCUGGGGAGAGAUAUUUUCUUAUGUUUAUUCGGAGAAUUUGGAGAAGUGAUUGAACUUUUCAAGACAUUGGAAACAAAUAGAACACAAUAUAAUUUACAUUAAAAAAUAAUUUCUACCAAAAUGGAAAGGAAAUGUUCUAUGUUGUUCAGGCUAGGAGUAUAUUGGUUCGAAAUCCCAGGGAAAAAAAUAAAAAUAAAAAAUUAAAGGAUUGUUGAUAACCCAGACUCAAAUAUCAUUGCCUUCCUCCAGGAGUAAUUAGGAACAGCUGAGGGCAUGCUGGGAGUAAGCAGCAAGAGUGCAUUCUGCUUUUAGAUUGAGGGAGAGGU